GUGGGCUGGAGGUGUGUCUUGAAUGCCCCCUCACCCCCAUGGGGAAGACCCACUUAGGGAAGACUCAAGUGUCUGUAUGGAGGAACCCACAUUCCCUGCCCCUCAGCUGUCCUCUGUCCCUUCCUAGCCCCCUCUGCUGUCCUGCAGGCUCUGGCGGUGGCCAUCCAGCUUGGUGGCCAUCUGGCUGAUCCACUCCUCCAGGUGGACCCUCUGUCCUCAUGUGGUGCAGGUCCCAUUGUGCCACCUCCAGACAGGCCAUGCUAGCCCCAGGGCCUCCGUUCCCUGUUACCCAGCCCCCACCCCCAGGUACGUGCCCCCUCCCUAAAGCCCACUGUGUCCACCAGCUGUGUUUCAACUCUGUCUCUGAGCAAGGCCUAACGCAAAGCCUGAAACAGCCUGGCUUGUAGAGGGCCAGGAGACCAAAGCUUGAAGAGAGAGUGACGGUCUCCCAGAGCCCACUUAGCCUCAGCCCCAGGGCUGUGUCCAUGCUGUUCCUGGCUCCAGUGAGCCAAUUCUCUCCCAUGACGCCUGUAAGGGCUCCAGUGGUGAUGGAGGUAGCUGGAGAGAACAAGGCUGUCUUAACCCUCCCUCCCUGAGAAGGCCCAACGGGGAACGUUUUAGGCAUCAGGGCAUUCUGGGGGGCAUCUUCCAGGGACCCCUCCUAUACCCUGCCCUGCCCUGGCUCUCUAGUGAGAAAUUGCAGUUGCUUGGACAGUGGGGCUGACCCAGGACAAAUGCAUAUAUUGGGCUGGUCUUCAGGGUGCUGGGGUAGGGGCAGGGGCACUUCAGGGAUAGGAAGGAGGGGCCUGUGUGUUCCAGAAGUACAGAGGAACCUGGUGCCGGCCGCAGUCAACCCCUAUGUGAUGAUCUUUCUACCCGCCCUCUUUCGUGUCUUGGUGCUGGCUGCUGUCUUUGGCCAGUGUGGCCCUGGUUACGCCUCCUCUGGCUCAGUCACACAGCAGCCUUGUAGGUGACUGGAGGUGUUCGCUGAUGUGGCCCCAACCCUACCUCCCUCCCCACCCCAUGAUGUUAGAAGAAUCUCGACAGAAUAAAUUGGCAGCAGCCAAGAAAAAGCUAAAAGAAUAUCAGCAAAGGAAGAGCCCUGGUAUUCCAGCAGGAGCAAAGACAAAAAAGAAAAAAACUGACAGUAGCCCUGAGACAACCACUUCCGGUGGUGGCCACUCACCUGGGGAUAGCCAGUACCAAGAACUAGCAGUAGCCCUGGAGUCAAGCUCAGUGACAAUCAAUCAGCUCAAUGAAAACAUAGAAUCAUUGAAACAGCAGAAGAAACAAGUGGAACAUCAGCUGGAAGAAGCAAAGAAAACAAACAAUGAAAUACACAAAGCACAAAUGGAGCAGUUAGAGACAAUCAACAUCCUCACAUUGGAAAAGGCAGACUUGAAGACCACCCUUUACCAUACUAAACGUGCUGCCCGACACUUCGAAGAAGAGUCCAAGGAUCUGGCUGGCCGCCUGCAAUACUCCUUACAGCAUAUUCAAGAAUUGGAGCGGGCUCUCUGUGCUGUGUCUACACAGCAGCAGGAAGAGGACAGGUCCUCGAGCUGCAGAGAAGCGGUCCUCCAGCGGCGGUUACAGCAGACCAUAAAGGAGCGGGCGCUGCUGAACGCACACGUGACACAGGUGACAGAGUCACUAAAACAAGUCCAGCUAGAGCGAGACGAAUAUGCUAAACACAUAAAAGGAGAGAGGGCCCGGUGGCAGGAGAGGAUGUGGAAAAUGUCGGUGGAGGCUCGAACAUUGAAGGAAGAGAAGAAGCGUGACAUACAUCGGAUACAGGAGCUGGAGAGGAGCUUGUCCGAACUCAAAAACCAGAUGGCUGAGCCCCCAUCCCUGGCACCCCCAGCAGUGACCUCUGUGGUGGAACAGCUACAAGAUGAGGCCAAACACCUGAGGCAGGAGGUGGAAGGUCUGGAGGGAAAGCUCCAGUCCCAGGUGGAAAACAAUCAGGCCUUGAGUCUCCUUAGCAAGGAACAAAAGCAGAGACUCCAGGAGCAGGAGGAGAUGCUCCGAGAGCAGGAGGCGCAGAGAGUGCGGGAGCAGGAGAGACUGUGUGAACAAAACGAGAGGCUUCGGGAGCAGCAGAAGACGCUACAGGAGCAGGGUGAGAGGCUGCGAAAGCAGGAGCAGAGGCUACGCAAACAGGAGGAGAGGCUGCGAAAGGAGGAGGAGAGGCUGCAAAAGCAGGAAAAGAGGCUGUGGGACCAGGAGGAGAGGCUGUGGAAGAAGGAGGAGAGGCUACAAAAGCAGGAGGAGAGGCUCGCGCUCUCCCAGAACCACAAGCUCGACAAGCAGCUGGCCGAGCCACAGUGCAGCUUCGAGGAUCUGAACAACGAGAAAAAGAGCGCACUGCAGUUGGAGCAGCAAGUAAAGGAGCUGCAGGAGAAGCUAGACGAGGAGCACCUAGAAGCUGCCAGCCAGCGGAACCAACAGCUAGAGACCCAGCUAAGCCUCGUGGCUCUCCCUGGAGAAGGAGAUGGAGGACAACAUCUGGACAGUGAGGAGGAGGAGGCGCCUCGGCCCACGCCAAACAUCCCAGAGGACCUGGAGAGCCGGGAGGCCACGAGCAGCUUUAUGGACCUCCCGAAGGAGAAGGCGGACGGGACGGAGCAGGUGGAGAGACGAGAGCUUGGAUUCGUCCAGCCUUCUGGAGUGACAGACGGCAUGAGAGAGUCCUUCACCGUAUAUGAAAGCCAGGGGGCAGUGCCAAACACGCGGCACCAGGAGAUGGAGGAUGUCAUCAGGCUGGCCCAGAAGGAGGAGGAGAUGAAGGUGAAGCUGCUGGAGCUGCAAGAGUUGGUGUUGCCCCUUGUGGGCAACCAUGAGGGGCAUGGCAAAUUCCUCAUCGCUGCCCAGAACCCUGCUGAUGAGCCCACUCCAGGGGCCCCAGCCCCCCAGGAACUUGGGGCUGCCGGUGAGCAGGAUGUUUUUUAUGAAGUGAGCCUGGACAACAACGUGGAGCCUGCACCAGGAGUGGCCAGGGAGGGUUCUCCCCAUAACAACCCCACUGUACAGCAGAUCGUGCAGCUGUCUCCUGUCAUGCAGGACACCUAGGAGCACCCAGGCUUGCCCAGCAAACCCUGCGUGCCAUUCUUCUACCAGGCAGCCGAGAACAGGGAGAUAAACAUCAUCAUCUUCUAAGAGCUGGUCAAGAAAUUUAAAACAACAACAACAACAAAAAGUUACGGGGUUCAUCUCCUACACAAUUCAUUUACUCCAUUUGAAUGCUAGAGCCACUCACUUUUAUUUGUGUUUCUAAUUUACCGUUUAAAUUUAUUUGUAAAAAGUUAAGGGAGAGUUGGUCUUUCCCUGAUGUUCUUUCUGGCAUCCUUUAGCAUUUUUAUUUUUAAUUUGAUAAUUGUAGGUCAUUAGUAUGCAUAUCGAGUUUGCCCUUAGGUGGUGGGAAUUCAAACACACAAAGACCCACUAAUUUGCACAAAACUAUUCUGGCUGGUUUGGAACAGGCUGCCAUGCUUUUUUAAUGUUAUUGCAGCAUGUAUAUUCAUUCCAGAAUUCAGAUAAAAUGUGCUUAUGUUCUGCUAUUACGUUUGAUCGAAUCCUAACCACAGUGAGCUCUUCAUUAGCUCAAUAUGUGGUUUGCCCUCAAUUGAGCACUGUUUAUUACUUUGUAAUAUGCCACUGUGAGUACUGACAUUUAGAGUUGUUUAAAGGCCAAGAACUGGAAACAGCCUUUUCCCUAUUUUCUGUGUAUUGGGGAUGGGAGUAAUAACAUUUUGGGGAGCUUUUUAAAUCUCACAGAAGAGGAAAGUGGCCUGCUCUGGCAGGUGUGUGCAGGAUAGAGUGUGUUUCAUUUGUUCUGGUGCCAAGAAUGAGCGCUGCACUAUGGUAGUUCCCUUAGGAUUUGUAUGUGCUCUGGGCUCAUGAAGAUAUUGCAUCAUGAGCUGCAGCAGUUGUACCCUUUCUUGAUGACCUAAAAAGGGAUUAUUUCUGAGGAAUGAAAGGCUCCCAUCAUUGACUGUGGAUGUGGAAAACCUUUUCUAGCUUAGAGCAUUUAUAUCUACAAUACAUUUUAAAGUCAGAGUUCAUGUUACCUGUUUUAAUCACAUGAGUAUAUGUCCCAGUACACAAAAGGGCACUGGUUGGCAUUC